CAGUUAAUAGAUAGAUAGAAAGAAAGAAUUCAUUGUUAACAGCAUAUAGUAUUUGAAAGCAAGUGCUGUAUUAAGAGAAUAAAAGGAAGCAUUGGUAAUUGAAGGUAAAUUGAUGCCUUUGUAACAAUAACUUGGCAGUUCUGCAAAGCUAAAUGUUUUUUAUAGCCAGUCAUGAGUAGACUGCAAAAUUUCGAGAGUUCAGUCUUGGCAAUCUGCAAAUGAAUCUGCAUGACAUUUGAUUUCAAACAAUCUUUCCUUUGAAGCUACCAGGAGUUUCUUUCAAGCAUACUUCCAGCCAUUGGUGCUCCCAUCCUCCUUGACUCAAAUAGGCACAAAUAUGACCAUUCAUUUUUCCUUUACUUUCCCCAGAAAUGUGAUUGUUUUCACUGCUCUUUUACUGUUUUCCUCUUAAGAUAAAUCUAGUAAUGAUUUCAUAAGAUGACCAUAAUGCAGAAUGUUUUCCUCAAUAUCUGCCUUAGUGUAAUGUAAUUCUGAUGCAGAAUGAUGGCAAAGUUUUAAUUAGCAACAUUUAAGCUAUAAGAAAUAACCAAUUGACCUUGGCAAUUAUUCCAUUUAUUUGUUCAACAAAUAUUAUAUUAAGCACUUAUUAUGUGCUACAAGUUUUGCUACAUGGUGGAGAUGAUUAGCAAGACACAGUCCUUAUCAUCUAAGGACUUGCAGUCGAGUGAAGUGACAAAUAGGUGCCCUAAAAUAUAAUAGGUAUUCUUCUAGAAAUCAGAAUUCAGUGAAGACCCAAAAGAAGUAGUGGUCAGGUCUAAGGUAGGGAUGUUGAGAAUGGAGAAUAAUAGAGCAAGCUGGAAAGGAUUCAUAGAAAAGGCAAUAUUGAACUGAAUCCUUUAAAAAAAAAAGAGAGAGACGGGGAAAGAAAGGCAAGAAAUACCAUUAAUAAAGUAGAGUCUUUGUAGGCUUUUUCAAUGUAAAAGAGAUCUGAAGAGGUCAGAGAGGACCCUGAUGAGACUGCCUUAAAUGACUUGCUGAAAAGUUCGACCUCUAACCUGUGAUGGGCAUUAAGAAGGGUGGCCAUAUGACCAAAUUGACAUUCUGGAAAGCAAGAUGUGUAAAAGGCCCAUUAGAAGAUUAUUAUACCGGUCCAGAAGAGAGAUGAUAAUGACCAAACCAAGACAAUGAAGAGGAGAAGUCAAAUGUGAGAUUUUAUGAUUGCAAAAUCUGUAGGAUAUGGUGAAUGCUGGAAGGGUAUAGUGAACUACUGAGUUCCUCUCAGUGAGAGGGCAUCUCUGGGUACAGCCAGGUUGGGGAGAAAUGAAUUUUCUUGGCCUUGUAGAUCAGGAGCUUAGGAUGAGUCUGGGCUAGAGACAAUGCUUUGGAGCUUGGCAGCCUCUGGUAGUGGUUGAAGCUAUGGGAAUGGGUGAGAUUGCCCAGGAAGGCUUGUAGGGUAAGAAGGAAAUGGGCUGAAGGCAGAGCUGUGAAGGUCACAAAUACGUAAGGGGUAUGCAAGGGGAGAGGAAUGGCAGGAACAGGCUGUCAGUUGUCUAGCAAAUGAAUUGUAUGUGUUGGGUGGAGGGGUAGAUGUGAGUGAAAUAAUGCAGAUUGCCACUGUUGAUAGGACUAACAAAGCUCCAGUUCCACCAUACCACCAAGGUACCAGUGAGUAUUUUAUGGGAGAAAAACUGAAAUUACCCCAUUCAGUAGGGGAGGUAAUUUUCAAGGCUUUUAAUUUCCUGCUAAGUUGCUAAAUCACAAGAGAUUGUUUUAAAGGAUACUCUUCCCUCUUUCCUUAUUUGGAAGAAAUUCUGUAGGCAGAAAGUUAUUCUCAGAGCCCUGGGCUGUGAGAACCUCCUUUAACCAUUCAUCACAACAGCUCUGAGUAAAUGAGAUAUAUUUUUAUGGCCAAGGAGUCCAAAGAGCCACUGACUGGGUAACAAUUAAUUAAGCUAGUAACUGACCUCCUUUAUCUCUGAGUGGCCUCUAUUCCAACCCUUUUUAUUUAGAGACCUGAAAUGCUUCAUACUAUUGGAUGGCACAUUCUAUAACUCUUACUGGGGUCUCCUCCUGGAAGUGGCCAUGCUGAACUGGACACAUCUGAGUAAUCCAUGGAAAGUUCCAUGGGUUCUCCUUUUUGCAUGGGUCCUAUUUUCUGGGAUAGGUAUAUCCAUACCUUCCUAACCAACAGGGGACGGGGUAGAACCAGGGCUGUGGGAACUCCCUAAGUGUCAAAUGGAAUUUUCAAGAGAUGACCCUAAUCUUUUUCCAAUUGUUUUAUCAAGGUGUCUGUACUAGGAUAAGGAAUUCCUAGUCUCUGUUCCUAAACUUUGUUCCAAAUGGUUACGUGGUUGCAGUUCUCCGGGAAUUGACCUUUAGAAGGAAGACACUAAAACAUCAGAAUGUGCAACAACGAGAGUGAGUGGUCCCAGAUCCACGAGAACAUCAUCCGAAAGUCCAGUGCCAAGUACUCUGCCCCCAGCGCCAGCCAUGGUCUUAUCAUUUCUCUGCAGCUUCUUCGUGGAGACAUGGAACAGAUUCGGAGAGAAAAUCCCAUGAUAUUUAAUAGGGGAUUGGCAAUUACAAGAAAAUUGGGAUUUCCUGAUGUCAUUAUGCCAGGUGAUAUCCGCAAUGACCUGUACCUAACCCUGGAGAAGGGGGAUUUCGAGAGAGGAGGAAAGAGUGUACAAAAGAAUAUUGAAGUGACCAUGUAUGUGCUUUAUGCAGAUGGAGAAAUCUUGAAGGAUUGCAUCAGCUUGGGUUCAGGAGAGCCAAAUAGGAGUUCCUACCACUCCUUUGUCCUCUACCACAGUAAUAGUCCUCGCUGGGGAGAAAUUAUCAAAUUGCCUAUCCCCAUUGACCGGUUCCGGGGCUCCCACCUGCGCUUUGAGUUCAGACAUUGUUCCACAAAGGACAAAGGGGAAAAGAAACUCUUUGGCUUUGCAUUCUCAACCCUGAUGCGUGAUGAUGGCACCACCCUCUCAGAUGAUAUUCACGAGCUUUAUGUGUACAAGUGUGAUGAGAAUAGCACGUUUAAUAACCAUGCUCUGUACCUGGGCCUGCCCUGCUGCAAAGAGGACUACAAUGGCUGCCCUAAUAUUCCUUCUAGCCUCAUCUUCCAGCGCAGCACCAAAGAGUCUUUCUUCAUCUCCACUCAGCUCUCCUCUACCAAACUCACCCAGAAUGUGGACCUCCUAGCUCUGCUGAAGUGGAAAGCCUUCCCCGACCGGAUCAUGGAUGUACUAGGGCGGCUGCGGCAUGUCAGUGGGGAGGAAAUUGUUAAGUUUCUGCAGGACAUCUUAGAUACACUCUUUGUGAUUUUGGAUGAUAAUACAGAGAAGUACGGCCUGUUGGUUUUUCAGUCUCUGGUGUUCAUCAUCAACCUGCUCCGAGACAUCAAGUAUUUUCACUUUCGACCUGUGAUGGACACGUAUAUCCAGAAGCACUUUGCUGGAGCUCUGGCAUACAAGGAGCUCAUCCGCUGUUUGAAGUGGUAUAUGGACUGCUCAGCAGAACUGAUUCGACAGGACCACAUUCAAGAAGCUAUGCGGGCCUUGGAGUACCUUUUCAAGUUCAUUGUACAGUCACGGAUCCUGUACUCACGAGCCACUUGUGGAAUGGAAGAGGAACAAUUCAGAUCCAGUAUCCAAGAACUUUUCCAGUCCAUCCGGUUUGUGCUCAGUCUGGACAGCCGAAACUCAGAAACACUCCUUUUUACUCAGGCUGCACUCCUCAAUUCUUUCCCAACCAUCUUUGAUGAGCUUCUGCAAAUGUUCACCGUGCAAGAGGUGGCAGAGUUUGUGAGAGGGACACUGGGGAGCAUGCCCAGCACUGUGCACAUUGGGCAGUCAAUGGACGUGGUCAAGCUGCAGUCCAUUGCCAGGACAGUGGAUAGCCGCCUGUUUUCUUUCUCAGAAUCCCGCCGCAUCCUGCUUCCUGUGGUUCUCCAUCACAUUCACCUUCACCUGAGGCAGCAGAAAGAGCUGCUAAUUUGCUCAGGGAUUCUUGGCAGCAUCUUCUCCAUCGUCAAGACCAGCUCUCUGGAGGCAGAUGUCAUGGAGGAAGUAGAGAUGAUGGUGGAGAGCCUCCUGGACGUGCUCUUGCAGACUCUGCUCACCAUCAUGAGCAAAUCGCACGCUCAGGAGGCGGUAAGAGGGCAGCGGUGCCCGCAGUGCACAGCCGAGAUCACUGGCGAGUAUGUGUCCUGCCUUCUCUCACUGCUCCGCCAGAUGUGUGACACCCAUUUCCAGCACCUCCUGGACAACUUCCAGAGCAAAGAUGAACUCAAGGAAUUUCUGCUGAAGAUUUUUUGCGUGUUCCGGAACCUGAUGAAGAUGAGUGUCUUCCCUCGGGACUGGAUGGUAAUGAGACUGCUCACAAGCAAUAUUAUAGUCACUACUGUCCAGUACCUGUCCUCUGCACUGCACAAGAAUUUCACAGAGACUGACUUUGACUUUAAGGUGUGGAAUUCUUACUUUAGCCUGGCAGUUCUAUUCAUAAAUCAGCCAAGCCUUCAGCUAGAAAUUAUCACCUCAGCCAAAAGGAAGAAGAUUCUAGAUAAGUAUGGGGACAUGCGUGUAAUGAUGGCCUAUGAACUGUUCAGCAUGUGGCAGAAUUUGGGUGAACAUAAGAUCCACUUUAUUCCGGGAAUGAUUGGUCCUUUUCUGGGUGUGACACUGGUCCCACAGCCAGAAGUACGGAAUAUCAUGAUUCCCAUCUUUCAUGACAUGAUGGACUGGGAGCAGAGAAAAAAUGGCAACUUCAAACAGGUGGAGGCCGAGUUGAUUGACAAGCUGGACAGCAUGGUGUCAGAAGGGAAAGGUGACGAGAGCUACAGGGAGCUCUUCAGCCUACUAACCCAGCUGUUUGGGCCCUACCCCAGCCUGCUGGAGAAGGUUGAACAAGAAACAUGGCGCGAGACCGGCAUUUCCUUUGUGACCUCAGUCACCCGCCUCAUGGAACGUCUUCUUGACUACAGGGACUGCAUGAAAGGAGAGGAAACAGAGAAUAAGAAGAUAGGCUGCACUGUUAACCUGAUGAAUUUUUACAAAUCUGAGAUUAACAAGGAAGAAAUGUAUAUCCGCUACAUCCAUAAGCUUUGUGACAUGCACUUGCAGGCCGAAAACUACACAGAGGCCGCAUUUACCCUGCUCCUUUACUGUGAGCUGCUGCAGUGGGAGGACCGGCCACUACGGGAAUUCCUCCACUACCCAUCGCAGACAGAGUGGCAGCGGAAGGAGGGACUGUGCCGGAAGAUCAUUCACUACUUCAACAAAGGCAAGAGCUGGGAGUUUGGGAUCCCACUGUGCAGGGAGCUGGCGUGUCAGUACGAGAGCCUCUAUGAUUACCAGAGCCUCAGCUGGAUUCGGAAAAUGGAGGCCAGCUACUAUGACAACAUUAUGGAGCAGCAACGCCUGGAGCCUGAGUUCUUUCGGGUCGGCUUCUAUGGCAGGAAGUUUCCUUUCUUUCUUCGGAACAAAGAAUACGUGUGCCGUGGCCAUGACUACGAGAGGCUGGAGGCCUUCCAGCAGAGGAUGCUCAGUGAGUUUCCGCAGGCUGUCGCCAUGCAGCACCCCAACCAUCCUGAUGACGCCAUCCUACAGUGCGAUGCCCAGUACUUGCAGAUCUAUGCAGUGACGCCCAUUCCAGAUUAUGUGGAUGUUCUGCAGAUGGAUAGGGUACCAGAUCGAGUCAAGAGCUUCUAUCGCGUCAACAAUGUGAGGAAGUUCCGGUAUGACAGGCCUUUUCACAAAGGCCCCAAGGACAAGGAGAAUGAAUUCAAGAGCCUGUGGAUUGAACGUACCACACUGACCCUGACCCACAGCUUGCCUGGCAUCUCUCGGUGGUUUGAAGUGGAGAGGAGGGAACUGGUGGAGGUGAGCCCUCUGGAGAAUGCCAUCCAAGUGGUUGAGAAUAAGAACCAGGAGCUACGCUCCCUGAUCAGCCAGUAUCAACACAAGCAGGUGCAUGGCAACAUUAACCUGCUAAGCAUGUGCCUGAAUGGUGUCAUUGAUGCAGCUGUCAAUGGAGGCAUUGCACGCUAUCAGGAGGCCUUCUUUGAUAAAGAUUACAUCAACAAGCACCCAGGAGAUGCUGAGAAGAUCACCCAGCUCAAGGAGCUUAUGCAGGAGCAGGUUCAUGUCCUUGGAGUUGGGCUAGCAGUUCAUGAGAAGUUUGUGCACCCAGAAAUGCGGCCUCUGCAUAAGAAGCUAAUUGAUCAGUUCCAGAUGAUGCGGGCCAGUCUCUACCAUGAGUUUCCAGGUUUGGAUAAGCUAAGUCCUGCAUGUUCAGGCACCAGCACCCCACGGGGAAAUGUUCUGGCAUCCCAUAGCCCCAUGAGUCCGGAGAGCAUCAAGAUGACCCACCGGCACAGCCCCAUGAACUUGAUGGGCACAGGCCGCCAUUCAUCAUCCUCUCUCUCCUCACAUGCGUCUAGUGAAGCAGGAAACAUGGUGAUGCUGGGUGACGGCUCCAUGGGUGAUGCUCCUGAGGACCUGUACCACCACAUGCAGCUCGCGUAUCCCAACCCCAGGUACCAAGGCUCAGUCACCAACGUCUCUGUUCUGUCCUCGUCCCAGGCAAGCCCUUCUUCCUCCAGCCUGAGUUCCACUCACUCAGCACCAUCCCAGAUGAUUACCUCUGCCCCUUCCAGUGCCCGAGGCUCUCCCUCUCUGCCAGAUAAGUACCGCCAUGCCCGUGAAAUGAUGUUGUUGCUGCCCACAUACCGGGACCGCCCAAGCAGUGCCAUGUAUCCAGCAGCCAUCCUGGAGAACGGACAGCCGCCGAAUUUCCAGCGAGCCCUGUUCCAGCAAGUGGUCGGAGCCUGCAAACCCUGCAGUGAUCCCAAUCUGUCUGUGGCUGAAAAAGCUGUGCCAGCAGCCCCCAGCAGCUGGAGUCUGGAUAGCGGAGCCCAAGAGGCCCAGCCCUUCCUGUCUGCCCAUAUGGGGCGCAUCCUGGCCCCCCCAGUGCCUCCCCGAAGCCUGCUGCAUGGUCAUUACUCCCUACACUUUGACGCCUUCCACCACCCUCUGGGUGAUACCCCCCCAGCCCUCCCUGCCCGGACCCUGCGCAAGUCUCCUCUCCACCCUAUCCCAGCCUCCCCCACAAGCCCCCAGUCAGGUCUGGACGGCAGCAACUCUACGCUGUCCGGCAGUGCCAGCAGCGGCGUGUCCUCCUUGAGUGAGAGUAACUUUGGGCACUCCUCGGAGGCCCCACCUCGCACUGACACCAUGGACUCCAUGCCAAGUCAGGCCUGGAAUGCUGACGAAGAUCUUGAGCCACCCUACCUCCCUGUCCACUACAGCCUCUCUGAGUCUGCCGUCCUGGACUCCAUCAAGGCCCAGCCAUGCCGAAGCCACUCAGCCCCAGGGUGCGUCAUCCCUCAGGACCCCAUGGACCCGCCUGCGCUGCCGCCCAAGCCCUACCACCCCCGCCUGCCGGCCCUGGAGCACGAUGAGGGGGUGCUGCUGCGUGAAGAGACUGAGAGGCCUCGAGGCCUGCACCGCAAGGCUCCAUUGCCUCCUGGGAGCGCUAAGGAGGAGCAGGCCCGCAUGGCCUGGGAGCACGGCCGAGGGGAGCAGUGAGGGGCAACGAGGCGGCUGGGAUGCCGCCCUCAGUAAGCAGCUUGCCAAUCACUCCAGGUCUGAAAAGCAAGUCCCCCAGCCCCACCCCAGGGAGCCAGAGAGGCUUGCACUCAGGAGAGAACCACCCCCAAGUCUCCGUUCUACUGCCGUGAACUCAUGUGUUGCCAUGUACAGAGGCCACAGCAGCAUGAAGGGUUGUGGCUUCCCUUUUUAUUUUUUUACAUUUCCAUUUCUAUGGGUUUUCCUUUCUUUCCUUUAUGCAGUAGAUGCUUUCUUCCUCCUGCAGUUCUGGACCAUGUGGAGCUACAUGGAGAAAUUGCACAGACAGAAUCACUUUGCCACACUGCAGGGCCCAGGAGUGGGAGCCCAGGCCCUCCCUCCAGGGUAGAGAUGCACCGAAUGGAAAUUGCACUAAGGACCUCUUCCUUUGCUGUAUGGACAGAAGAGUUCAUGGUUGCAUUCAGGGAUUGCAAGGACCAUAUAGACAUGUCACAGGUGGAAAAAGGGCCACAAGCCGUUUUGCACAAAUGCCUGCCCACCUGCCCCUCUUCCAUCCAGGAGUGUGCUACUGAGGGGCUGGCUGGACCAACCUGCUGGCUCAGGCAUGUGACUGGCCUAACUGCAUGCCCAGGGCACUGCCAGGGUUCAAUGGGCCAGCCGUCUCCUACUCCACCUUGGAUUUUUCUCUCCAUCACAUCAUUUCUGACCAUUUGCUCCCUUCCAUUCUUGAAACACCUCAUGCCCCACAGGAGCCCCAGUGGUGACUGGAUCUGCAAGGGUUAUCUCCCGCCCUCUGGGGUUUGAGUGGAGGUAUGGAGCCAGAGAGGCUAUCCUAGCUACCUUCCUCCUAGGGGGAGCUGGUCCCCUUCCUAUGUGGUAGAGAGACUGGUGUAAGAGUGUGGGGUGUGGCAGGCGCCGGAAAUCCUCAAAGCUUUCAGAAGCAUCCAGAAUGCCUACCAUCAGCUCCUGAAUCAGGGAUUUUCAGCACUACCUCUGAGCCAUGGGGUUGGCUGCCCAGCCAGGCUUCCAGGCCCUGAGGACAUGUGGUCAGGUUCAGCAGGCUCCUGGGUAAAGAGGGUGGGAGGGGGCUUCUCCUUUUGGAAGCAGAUAGCCAUGCAGGUAGAAUUGUCAUCUCCCAAGUGGCCACAUACAGCAACCCACUCCAGGCCAUGGGGACCACCACUCAGGGUUCGGGGCUGGCAGGAGGGUAGUUUCUCCAGUCUCCCCAGUCUGUUGGUGUCUUUAUAGGAAACUAUAAAGCAGAGCAGUGGUGUCUUUAGAGGAAACUCAUUCAAGUCAGGGCACUGAUUUUCCUCUCAGUUUAUUAUUUGGGGGGAUAGGGUCAGGUGGGUAUAGUAGUACUUUACCAGGGUGCUUUUAAGUUACUUUAAAAAAAGCCUACAAAAUAUUUUUUUUCUUUUAUUUGCUCGAGUUCACAUUAAUGAUGGUCACAAGGCUGCCUUGUUGGGCAGGCGUAUUGCCCCCAGUUCCUCUUCUGCUGGCCUGUAUGACCUCCACAGCCAGGCCCUGGGCCCAAGCCCCUUGUCCCUUCUCCACUGCCCCUCUUUCCAGACAGUAAAGGCCAUGGUCAGUGUGUUUUUCUCUUGUAAACAAACCCCAGCUUGUUUAACAGAAAUGCUAAUAACCUACUGGGAAAGAUGGAGGUCUAAAUUACCUCCAGGGUUUUUCUGGGGGUUUAUCACCAGUGUGGGUCCCUUCUGAUACCACCAGGUUCACUCCAGGCAGAGUGGGGCGGAAGGCUGCUGAGGAUAUGGGUCAGUUACAGCAGCCCUCACCUCAAAGGGCUGGCCUGCUUCUCAGCCUACAUUCAUUUGCAAGCUUCAAUCUCUGGACCAUCUGGUGUUCACAGGUGUUAGAGGGUUAGGGGUUAGGGGCUAGUUUUGGAUUUGAUUCAUAGGUAGGAGGGCUUAGAUUUUAAGGCACUUCUGAAAGUCAAUCCCUGGACAAGGCAGUCAUCACAUAAGAACAGCUACCUUCUCCACUUGGUGGCACAAGAGGUAGGGAGGGGAGUAUGGGUUCAUUUGGCUUCGCAUUAUGCAAGGUGAAACCGUUUGUUUUCCCUCUCCAUUUUCCCUAACUAAAUGAAAAGGACACAUUCUGAAAUCCCUUUUGUUGGAGAAUAAGUCAGUCUGAGGGGAAAUGGGAGGCCAGAGAUGAGAACCCUUUGAAAAGAUUGUAAAAUACUGAUUUUCAUUCUUUCAAGCUUAUUUGUAAAUACCUAUUUGAAUGCUGUGUAUUUGUACAGGAAUUUGAGCAAAAAAUGUAUAGAGUGUGAUGUCCAAUUGGUAUUCAGCACUAUAAAUGUGUUUUUAACCUCCCGCAUUCUGUGCUUAUUUAAAACAAGGAAACUUCUAACCAUUUCUUUUGUGUAUUCAUGUUUAAAGAAAAAAAGUGAUUUAAAAAUGAUCUUACCUGUACCAGAAAAGCAAAGUUAAAGGAAACAAAAUUUGUACCAUUGUCCCAAGAGGUAUUUUACUGUAUAUAUUGUGGUAGCAUGUUCAAAAUCCAACAAGUAAUGUGAAUUUUAGAUGUAAAUAUCUGCCACUUGAUUUUUUUUCCCCCUUUCCCCACUUCCUUGACUGCUGUGAUGUGAAUUAAAGAUAAAUACGUGAUACUGA